UUCAAUUAAUGAACUUCUAUAUGGAUGUGGGGAAACCAACAAUGUUAUUCUCCCUCACAUUACACACAAAAGUAAUUUCAGCCGCAUUACACACCAAAACUUAAAAGUUAAAGAUAUAAAGCAUUUCAAGGAUACUUUGUGACUUGUUGGCAGGCAAAGAUUAGCCUACCAACAAGCAGGACACAGAAAAAAUACAUAUAUAAGAAAGACAUGAUAAAUGAGACUUCAUCAACAUUAGCCACACCUUCUCAUCAAAAGAUACCACUAAGAAAGCGAAAAGGCAAGCAAGCCACAGACAGAGAGAAAAUACCCACAAAACGUAUCUGACCUCCACACCCUGCAAUUAUAAUUAUAGUGGUCUGGUACACUGCACCCAGUUUCUGCUGGAUGGAGUAUUUUCUGGGUGUCUCUAAUGAGUAAGAGAGGGCCCCAUGGGAUAUUCCUUCAGUUCCCAGAUGAACAGUGGGAAAGACUCCACAUUGACCAACCUCGGGGGCCUGAAAACCCAGGUCCUCAAGGAGGGUAGAGUAUACCUGGACCCUGACCCAGACCCCUGGAUGGGCUGUGCCAAGAGACCCAGCAAGGGAAGGGAUUUCCUCCUGCCUCAGGUUCUCUGUUCUUCUGUGGUUAGACCACCUGAACCCAACUCCCUCCCCAAGCACUAGAGAUGGGCUUUUCCAAGGGCUGGGGAUCUUGCUGUCCUGAGGACAGCUGAGCAAGGGGGUCGAGGAGGAGCUUGGGUUGUGGAGGAGAGGAAACCGGGUAAGAUGCGUGAAGCAGUUGGCUAUACCAGGCACAGAGAGGACCCGCUGGGACCCAAGAGCCUGCAUGUGAAGCCAGGCCUUGGGCCACCUUGUCUGUCAAGGGGGUGCCUACUUCCAUGGUGUCUUCAAAGGGACUGUGGAAAGAGAGGCCUUCAGCCCACACCUCUGAAUGCUUUUCCACCACAGCAUGCCCUGUGGCCUUUAUCCUGCUGGUGUGGAACAGUCAGACCCCUGCAGGGCUGCAGAGCCUCUGUACUGGGCGGCAUCCCAGCCUGAGUGCCAGAGCUCAGAGGGCAGGCCCCCGAGCAAGCAGAGAGGAGGGCACCUUUUGGACAGAACGUGUGGGACAAGAGCGAUGGCUCAUCCGUUCAGGUUCCUCACAAAAUGAGAGUCAGGAAGAUCAGGGCGCCGGCCUGAUUUCCCAGGCAGGGCUGAAAGCAGACAACCGGAGGGAGAGCAGCACCUGGGCCAAUGAGGUAGAAGACAGAAGACCACAGUGUACUCCUGCCCUCAACCUCACCCCCUCCCACCCACAUCCUCCACACUCCCUGACCACCUUCCUCAGAAGUGUAAUAGGAAUCCAGAUUCCCCCUGGCCUGGUUGCUGCAGGAGGCACAGUAGCCUGA